AUGCGCAUAACGGCCGCCAUCUUAACAGCGCGUUCCCGUUGGCGUCUGAGGAACAGCAUCUCUGCCUUCCUGUUCACGGUGACCUUCGCUUGGUGUCCUCCUGGCCUCAGCAACCUGACAAUUCUGUCGUGUCCCGAGAGAUGGCUAAUGAAUGGCGCUUGAUGACAGAUGAGUAAUGCCUGUUGCUGAAAGAUUGACGGUAUGAGGCAAGACUCCCACUACUACUUAAUCAAGAGGAAUUGAGAUUGACUUACCCAUAAGUUCAGACAGUGUCUCGAAGAGACUUUGGGAACAAGAUAUUCAGGCACAUUUCACUGUUAGACUCACAGGAUGCUGGCCAUUGGUCUUUCCCUUUGUGAUCAUCUUUCUCAAGAUGUUUUCUGUCUUCAUGAGUCAAAAUUUGAAGAGGAAAGGAUGGUGGCUGGGUGGUUGACAAAUUACUCUCAGGACUCAGUGACCUUUGAGGAUGUGGCUGUGGACUUCACCCAGGAGGAGUGGACUUUGCUGGAUCAAACUCAGAGAAACUUAUACAGAGAUGUGAUGCUGGAGAACUAUAAGAAUCUAGUUGCAGUAGAUUGGGAGAGUCAUAUUAAUACCAAAUGGUCAGCACCUCAGCAGAAUUUUUUGCAGGGGAAAACAUCCAGUGUGGUGGAAAUGGGCUGGGUAUAAGUAAGCAAGAAGAGGGCCUGGGAGAAGAGUCUGACGAGCAAGGGGAAGGUAGCCAAGGAUGGAGUGAAAUACAGGAGAUGCGGUCUUGCUGUGUUGCCUAGGCUGGUCUCAAACUCCUGCUCUCAAGUGAUCCUCCUGCCUCAGCCUCCUGAGUACAUUUAUAUUUAAAGUAAUUAUUGAUGGCUCUGCCUGCUUAGGACUCUGCCCAGCCAGGAAGGAAACCUACAGGAGGAAGAAUGGCUGCAGGGUGGCUGACAACCUGGUCACAGAACUCAGUAACCUUCCAGGAAGUGGCAGUGGACUUUUCCCAGGAGGAGUGGGCAUUGCUGGACCCUGCUCAAAAAAAUCUAUACAAAGAUGUGAUGCUGGAGAACUUUAGGAACCUGGCCUCAGUAGGGUAUCAGCUCUGCAGACACAGUCUGAUCUCCAAGGUGGAUCAAGAACAGCUGAAGACAGAUGAAAGAGGAAUUUUACAAGGUGACUGUGCAGACUGGGAAACUCAACUUAAACCAAAAGAUACAAUUGCUAUGCAGAACAUUCCUGGGGGAAAAACAUCCAAUGGCAUAAACACGGCAGAAAAUCAACCUGGUGAGCACUCCCUGGAGUGUAACCAUUGUGGGAAAUUCAGAAAGAACACUCGCUUUAUUUGUACAAGAUAUUGCAAGGGAGAGAAAUGCUAUAAAUAUAUAAAGUAUAGCAAAGUCUUCAACCAUCCCUCAACUCUUAGGAGUCAUGUGAGCAUUCACAUUGGAGAGAAAACUCUUGAAUUUACUGAUUGUAGAAAAGCUUUCAAUCAAGAGUCAUCCCUCAGGAAACACUUAAGAACUCCCACAGGACAGAAGUUUCAGGAGUAUGAGCAAUGUGAUAUGUCCUUCAGCCUACACUCUUCCUGCUCAGUACGUGAGCAAAUACCUACUGGAGAGAAAGGUGAUGAAUGCAGUGACUAUGGCAAAAUAUCUCCCCUUAGUGUCCACACAAAAACUGGUAGUGUGGAGGAGGGUUUGGAAUGUAAUGAACAUGAGAAAACUUUCACUGACCCUUUGUCCCUUCAGAACUGUGUCAGAACUCACUCUGGAGAGAUGCCCUAUGAAUGCAGUGACUGUGGGAAAGCCUUCAUUUUUCAGUCUUCCCUUAAGAAACACAUGAGAUCUCAUACUGGAGAGAAGCCUUAUGAGUGUGAUCACUGUGGAAAAUCCUUUAGCCAGAGCUCUCAUCUGAAUGUGCACAAAAGAACUCACACUGGAGAGAAACCCUAUGACUGUAAGGAAUGUGGGAAGGCUUUCACUGUUCCUUCAUCCCUUCAGAAACAUGUGAGAACCCACACUGGAGAGAAACCCUAUGAAUGCAGUGACUGUGGAAAAGCCUUCAUCGAUCAGUCAUCCCUUAAGAAACACACACGCUCUCACACUGGAGAGAAGCCUUAUGAGUGUAACCAGUGUGGAAAGUCCUUCAGCACAGGCUCUUACCUUAUUGUGCACAAGAGAACUCACACUGGUGAGAAAACCUAUGAGUGUAAAGAAUGUGGGAAGGCCUUUAGGAAUUCCUCUUGCCUGAGGGUACACGUGAGAACUCACACUGGAGAGAAGCCUUAUAAAUGUAUUCAGUGUGAAAAAGCCUUUAGCACAAGCACUAACCUUAUAAUGCACAAGCGAAUCCACAAUGGCCAGAAACUCCAUGAAUGAAAUGACUCAGGGAAGUGUUUGUUGCCCCUCAUGCCUCCUUUCUCACUUUAGAACAUAUAUUGGAGAGAAGCCCUGUUAUGGUCACCUGGAAACAGCCUUCUGGCCCAACUCUGGAUGCCUGUUAUACUGGGACAAACCUUAUAAAUGUUAUAGCUAUGAUUGUUUUUAUCAGUGAGUAUUUCAUUCUUAUAUGUGUCACAACUGUAGAUCCUAUGAAUAUUUUAGUUAUCUUUUCAGUUUAAUUGCAUUGUGAACAGAACACAUGGUCUUCAAUAUGUAGAUUCUGUGUGACAUAGAUUUGAACAUAAUUGCUGGACACUGACUGAUGUACUGUGGCAGACAGAACUAGUUGCUGUCUCAAUAUCCAUUCCUCCCUUCUUUCUUAAAGUAAUAAAAUUUACCAUUUAGUUCAAGCUGGCAAUGUGGACAGUUUUCACCCAGCUUCCCUUACAGCUGUGAGCGGCCAAAUAUGUUCACAUCCCUAGCCCAUGCAAAGUAGGCAGAAGUCACUGGAUACAGCUGCUAAGGAAGCUCAUGGAAAUGGGAAUAUCUCAUCUGGUGUUUUUUUCUUAACUAUUUGCCCUUUGUCUUGUCCCUUAUUUCCUAGAAAAUAUAUACACCAAGAGGAGGACAGAGAAAGGAUACUAAAUGAAACAACAGGGGAGAUACAAUAUUAUCUGGUUGCACUAAUCCUGUGCUGCUUAUCUCUGGAUUUCAUGUUACAUGAGAAAAAUUAACUGCCAUGUGGUUUAAACCACUCUUGUGGGAAGUUCCUCUUUCAGCUGAUUUCAGUCCCAACUGUUACAUCUAAUAAAUGGUCAAGUUUUAGGAAUCGUUCAA